AAUCCUUUCUUUCAGCUGGAGUGCUCCUCAGGAGCCAGCCCCACCCUUAGAAAAGAUGUUUUCCAUGAGGAUCGUCUGCCUGGUCCUAAGUGUGGUGGGCACAGCAUGGACUGCAGAUAGUGGUGAAGGUGACUUUCUAGCUGAAGGAGGAGGCGUGCGUGGCCCAAGGGUUGUGGAAAGACAUCAAUCUGCCUGCAAAGAUUCAGACUGGCCCUUCUGCUCUGAUGAAGACUGGAACUACAAAUGCCCUUCUGGCUGCAGGAUGAAAGGGUUGAUUGAUGAAGUCAAUCAAGAUUUUACAAACAGAAUAAAUAAGCUCAAAAAUUCACUAUUUGAAUAUCAGAAGAACAAUAAGGAUUCUCAUUCGUUGACCACUAAUAUAAUGGAAAUUUUGAGAGGCGAUUUUUCCUCAGCCAAUAACCGUGAUAAUACCUACAACCGAGUGUCAGAGGAUCUGAGAAGCAGAAUUGAAGUCCUGAAGCGCAAAGUCAUAGAAAAAGUACAGCAUAUCCAGCUUCUGCAGAAAAAUGUUAGAGCUCAGUUGGUUGAUAUGAAACGACUGGAGGUGGACAUUGAUAUUAAGAUCCGAUCUUGUCGAGGGUCAUGCAGUAGGGCUUUAGCUCGUGAAGUAGAUCUGAAGGACUAUGAAGAUCAGCAGAAGCAACUUGAACAGGUCAUUGCCAAAGACUUACUUCCCUCUAGAGAUAGGCAACACUUACCACUGAUAAAAAUGAAACCAGUUCCAGACUUGGUUCCCGGAAAUUUUAAGAGCCAGCUUCAGAAGGUACCCCCAGAGUGGAAGGCAUUAACAGACAUGCCGCAGAUGAGAAUGGAGUUAGAGAGACCUGGUGGAAAUGAGAUUACUCGAGGAGGCUCCACCUCUUAUGGAACCGGAUCAGAGACGGAAAGCCCCAGGAACCCUAGCAGUGCUGGAAGCUGGAACUCUGGGAGCUCUGGACCUGGAAGUACUGGAAACCGAAACCCUGGGAGCUCUGGGACUGGAGGGACUGCAACCUGGAAACCUGGGAGCUCUGGACCUGGAAGUACUGGAAGCUGGAACUCUGGGAGCUCUGGAACUGGAAGUACUGGAAACCAAAACCCUGGGAGCCCUAGACCUGGUAGUACCGGAACCUGGAAUCCUGGCAGCUCUGAACGCGGAAGUGCUGGGCACUGGACCUCUGAGAGCUCUGUAUCUGGUAGUACUGGACAAUGGCACUCUGAAUCUGGAAGUUUUAGGCCAGAUAGCCCAGGCUCUGGGAACGCGAGGCCUAACAACCCAGACUGGGGCACAUUUGAAGAGGUGUCAGGAAAUGUAAGUCCAGGGACAAGGAGAGAGUACCACACAGAAAAACUGGUCACUUCUAAAGGAGAUAAAGAGCUCAGGACUGGUAAAGAGAAGGUCACCUCUGGUAGCACAACCACCACGCGUCGUUCAUGCUCUAAAACCGUUACUAAGACUGUUAUUGGUCCUGAUGGUCACAAAGAAGUUACCAAAGAAGUGGUGACCUCCGAAGAUGGUUCUGACUGUCCCGAGGCAAUGGAUUUAGGCACAUUGUCUGGCAUAGGUACUCUGGAUGGGUUCCGCCAUAGGCACCCUGAUGAAGCUGCCUUCUUCGACACUGCCUCAACUGGAAAAACAUUCCCAGGUUUCUUCUCACCUAUGUUAGGAGAGUUUGUCAGUGAGACUGAGUCUAGGGGCUCAGAAUCUGGCAUCUUCACAAAUACAAAGGAAUCCAGUUCUCAUCACCCUGGGAUAGCUGAAUUCCCUUCCCGUGGUAAAUCUUCAAGUUACAGCAAACAAUUUACUAGUAGCACGAGUUACAACAGAGGAGACUCCACAUUUGAAAGCAAGAGCUAUAAAAUGGCAGAUGAGGCCGGAAGUGAAGCCGAUCAUGAAGGAACACAUAGCACCAAGAGAGGCCAUGCUAAAUCUCGCCCUGUCAGAGACUGUGAUGAUGUCCUCCAAACACAUCCUUCAGGUACCCAAAGUGGCAUUUUCAAUAUCAAGCUACCGGGAUCCAGUAAGAUUUUUUCUGUUUAUUGCGAUCAAGAGACCAGUUUGGGAGGAUGGCUUUUGAUCCAGCAAAGAAUGGAUGGAUCACUGAAUUUUAACCGGACCUGGCAAGACUACAAGAGAGGUUUCGGCAGCCUGAAUGACGAGGGGGAAGGAGAAUUCUGGCUAGGCAAUGACUACCUCCACUUACUAACCCAAAGGGGCUCUGUUCUUAGGGUUGAAUUAGAGGACUGGGCUGGGAAUGAAGCUUAUGCAGAAUAUCACUUCCGGGUAGGCUCUGAGGCUGAAGGCUAUGCCCUCCAAGUCUCCUCCUAUGAAGGCACUGCGGGUGAUGCUCUGAUUGAGGGUUCCGUAGAGGAAGGGGCAGAGUACACCUCUCACAACAACAUGCAGUUCAGCACCUUUGACAGGGAUGCAGACCAGUGGGAAGAGAACUGUGCAGAAGUCUAUGGGGGAGGCUGGUGGUAUAAUAACUGCCAAGCAGCCAAUCUCAAUGGAAUCUACUACCCUGGGGGCUCCUAUGACCCAAGGAAUAACAGUCCUUAUGAGAUUGAGAAUGGAGUGGUCUGGGUUUCCUUUAGAGGGGCAGAUUAUUCCCUCAGGGCUGUUCGCAUGAAAAUUAGGCCCCUUGUGACCCAAUAGGCUGAAGAAGUGGGAAUGGGAGCACUCUGUCUUCUUUGCUAGAGAAGUGGAGAGAAAAUACAAAAGGUAAAGCAGUUGAGAUUCUCUACAACCUAAAAAAUUCCUAGGUGCUAUUUUCUUAUCCUUUGUACUGUAGCUAAAUGUACCUGAGACAUAUUAGUCUUUGAAAAAUAAAGUUAUGUAAGGUUUUUUUUAUCUUUAAAUAGCUCUGUGGGUUUUAACAUUUUUAUAAAGAUAUACCAAGGGCCAUUCAGUACAUCAGGAAAGUGGCAGACAGAAGCUUCUCUCUGCAACCUUGAAGACUAUUGGUUUGAGAACUUCUCUUCCCAUACCACCCAAAAUCAUAAUGCCAUUGGAAAGCAAAAAGUUGUUUUAUCCAUUUGAUUUGAAUUGUUUUAAGCCAAUAUUUUAAGGUAAAACUCACUGAAUCUAACCAUAGCUGACCUUUGUAGUAGAAUUUACAACUUAUAAUUACAAUGCACAAUUUAUAAUUACAAUAUGUAUUUAUGUCUUUUGCUAUGGAGCAAAUCCAGGAAGGCAAGAGAAACAUUCUUUCCUAAAUAUAAAUGAAAAUCUAUCCUUUAAACUCUUCCACUAGACGUUGUAAUGCACACUUAUUUUUUUCCCAAGGAGUAACCAAUUUCUUUCUAAAACACAUUUAAAAUUUUAAAACUAUUUAUGAAUAUUAAAAAAAGACAUAAUUCACACAUUAAUAAACAAUCUCCCAAGUAUUGAUUUAACUUCAUUUUUCUAAUAAUCAUAAACUAUAUUCUGUGACAUGCUAAUUAUUAUUAAAUGUAAGUCGUUAGUUCGAAAGCCUCUCACUAAGUAUGAUCUAUGCUAUAUUCAAAAUUCAACCCAUUUACUUUGGUCAAUAUUUGAUCUAAGUUGCAUCUUUAAUCCUGGUGGUCUUGCCUUCUGAUUUUUAAUUUGUAUCCUUUUCUAUUAAGAUAUAUUUGUCAUUUUCUCUUGAAUAUGUAUUAAAAUAUCCCAAGCAA